AGAAGCGCCUAAGAGAUGCGCAUGUAAGGGGUGCCAUGGAGCACCCGGGAAGGACCCAGGCCUGGGCAGGGAGGCGUUGGGGCCGGCUCUAGGGAGCAAAGCUGUCGGAGUCCAGGCCUCUAUCACCCGACUGCUGACACUGCCCUCCCAUCCCUGCUCUACAAGCGGGCGGUGGUGACUACACGAGGCGCCGAAGAUGCUGUUGAGGGCCCUGGAGAAACUUCAGCAGAACAGGGCCUCUCCCCUUGCAGGCCGAGCCGGGGGCCCUGCGCCCUCCCCCUCCGCCCAGCUCGGCCAAGGGCGCAUUUGCUGAGCGUCUGGCGGCCUCUACCGGAGCACCUCUGCAGAGGGCCGAUCCUCCAGCCCAGAGACGACAUGUGGCGCUCGGGCGAGGUGAGAGCGGGCGCGAGUGCGCCGGGGGCGCUGGGGGGCUCUGCGGCGGGCGGCGCGCGGCCCGGGGCGCGGCGCGGAGCGGAGCUGCAGGGCGGCGGCGGGAGCGCGGGGCGCAAGAGCCGCUCCGCCGGGAGUGCCGGGGAAGUUCGCGCUGGCAGCAUGGGGCGGUGACGCCGCACCGGCCUUCCGCGCCUGCCAGCCGGGCGAGAGCAGGCGGAGGAGAAGGAGGAUGCAUCCUCACCGACGGCUCGCCUCCCGGGGCCGGCGCGCAGGUGCCUUGCAGAGAGAGGAGUAGCUUGCUGGCUUUGAACGCGUGGCGUGGCAGAUAUUUCAGAAAGCUUCAAGAACAAGCUGGAGAAGGGAAGAGUUAUUCCUCCAUAUUCACCUGCUUCAACUACUAUUCUUAUUGGGAAUGGACAAUGGAAUGUUCUCUGGUUUUAUCAUGAUCAAAAACCUCCUUCUCUUUUGUAUUUCCAUGAACUUAUCCAGUCACUUUGGCUUUUCACAGAUGCCAACCAGUUCAGUGAAAGAUGAGACCAAUGACAACAUCACGAUAUUUACCAGGAUCUUGGAUGGGCUCUUGGAUGGCUACGACAACAGACUUCGGCCCGGGCUGGGAGAGCGCAUCACUCAGGUGAGGACCGACAUCUACGUCACCAGCUUCGGCCCGGUGUCCGACACGGAAAUGGAGUACACCAUAGACGUGUUUUUCCGACAAAGCUGGAAAGAUGAAAGGCUUCGGUUUAAGGGGCCCAUGCAGCGCCUCCCUCUCAACAACCUCCUUGCCAGCAAGAUCUGGACCCCAGACACGUUCUUCCACAACGGGAAGAAGUCCAUCGCUCACAACAUGACCACGCCCAACAAGCUGCUGCGGCUGGAGGACGACGGCACCCUGCUCUACACCAUGCGCUUGACCAUCUCUGCAGAGUGCCCCAUGCAGCUUGAGGACUUCCCGAUGGAUGCGCACGCUUGCCCUCUGAAAUUUGGCAGCUAUGCGUACCCUAAUUCUGAAGUCGUUUACGUCUGGACCAACGGCUCCACCAAGUCGGUGGUGGUGGCGGAAGAUGGCUCCAGACUGAACCAGUACCACCUGAUGGGGCAGACGGUGGGCACUGAGAACAUCAGCACCAGCACAGGCGAAUACACAAUCAUGACAGCUCACUUCCACCUGAAAAGGAAGAUUGGCUACUUUGUCAUCCAGACCUACCUUCCCUGCAUAAUGACCGUGAUCUUAUCACAGGUGUCCUUUUGGCUGAACCGGGAAUCAGUCCCAGCCAGGACAGUUUUUGGUCCCCUUGACAGAGAAAGUGUGCCUGAUUCUAUCCAAACAUGAGACAAGGUGCUGCUCCUUCCUACCCGCCAGCCCCCGAAUGCUCCUUUCCUCAUAUUCAAGGCCCUUACCAAGUCUUACUGACAACAGGUCCAAUUUCACUCCAGCAAAAGGCGAUGGGGUGUGAAUGGCUUGGCCCUAUUUAUAUUCAAGCCUAUUAUUUUGGCAGAAGUAACUCCUGCAUCUUGAGGGACGACUUGUCUGGUUUUAGUUGUGGAAUCUGUUCUUACGCUCAUUUUAUCUCAUUUCACCAUGCAGGGUGUCCUCUUCAGGUGGCCCUCAGGUCGAGAAGGGGGCACCAAUGUAAUGGAAGGAGUUCCUCAGCAAAGCACACCCAAGCCCCACCGAGUGCAUGAUUGAACCCCCUUACACCAGGCACAUAAAUUGUUGUGAAAGCAUUACUCUGUUCAAAGCAAAGAACCACCAAGUAUUUAAAGGAUGAUUUAUGCCCAAACAUUUGAAGAAAAAAUGUUAUUCCAAGCUGCACUGUUUCCUUGGGGAGAUAAGAAUAACAUUCGUGGACGGUAAAUAAAGCAGCAUGUGGUGAACGGCUAAUUUCGCCACACAGAAAACAAACACACAAAUCUCUGUAUGGAGAGAACAGGAGGUCAGAGCCAUCGGGGCGACCUGAAAGUAAAACUUAAUCUGUCCUUUGGAAAAUCAGCAUGAAGGGAGUCCUGGAAGGCAUUAGAGAGGCCUCGAAGUGUAAGUCCGACCUCCCAGCCAAGGGCCACAAGCCAGUUACAGCAGAGCAGGAGGCCCUGGUUCCACUGGGAGACCUGCUUCCAUCCCAUCCACAGCCCCGUGCUUGCUCUGAGGGUUUGACUCUGCUGUCAGGAGUUCUGGCCUGACCUCGCCUGUUGGGCCUUCACUAUUUCCAAGUGCCAGGAGCCCCUCCCCCACUGUAGUUUCAGCAUAGAAGCCCCACUUCCAAGCCUAGCUCCCAGGUUGGAGGAAGGCCUGGCAGGACCCAUUCUGGGUGCUCUCAUGAAGGGAGGAAAGGGGAAACCGGAGGAAGGGCCUCGGGCAUGGGUAUGCUUUGAGGGCUGAGAGGAGGGACAGGAGUGAUCUGACUGCACUGGGUGAUAGGGACUCGGGGGCUGGGAGCAGGCUGUUCUCAGACGAUAGAGGUUCUUGGCCGACACGUUUGAACUUGUUCCUGCAGACCAGGGGUCCAGAGAAGGUGCUGUGUGGGGAGGAACGAGAAUGGAGUCUGGGGAGACGGGGCUUCCCAACACCCUGCACUGUGUUGCUGGAAGGUGCUUGUUUGUCACCUGCCUGGGACAUAGAUGGUGCAUGAUGGAUAGUGGGCUGGAGCCUGGUCUGAGGUCAGGGAGGAGCCGGAAGUCCCUGGCAGUCACUGAGGUUGUUGGGCUCAUGCCUGUGAGUCUAGGAGGAACGUGAGCCCCCGGGUGAAUGGAGAGAGCACACCUGUGGCUGGGUGUUCUUGUUGGGUGUCGCCGACACUGUCAAUCACCAUGUCCGCCCUGCCUCCUGUGGCGGCUGAUCUAAUCACCAUAGAUCUGAAUUCUGAAUGGAGGGUUGGAGGGAGGAGAGAGGAUGAAAGUGACCUGCACUGUCUAAUCCGAGGAGAGAAAGGGUCUUCUAGAAUAAGCCGCGUGCCUCAAGCUGGCUUGUGGAAUGUUCAGACUCGUUCCUGGGAAGGCAGUGGCGCUGGGGGUUCCACCCCUGCUGCCAGGAAGGCUCUGCGUGCUGGAAGCCAUGGUGCAUCUGCAGGCAUGCAGGCCUCACACCCCGCGGUCAGACACUGGCGCGAGCGUGAAUACCACAGCCUGGUGUCAGCCUACUCGAGUAAACUGUUCCAUGGAAGUAGAGAGGACUUUAAAAAAAUAGACUGUGUUCACCAUUGUUCCAAGUUGGGAUCUCCAGAAGCAAACACUGGGUCAGAGUUUGGGGUGUAAGGCAGUUUUUAGGAGUGAACGUUUGGGAAAGGAAACAGGAGGCAGUGAGAUUCAGAGAGGAAGAGAUCGAACCAUGAUGCAGGCCCAGCAAAGCCCAGGCUAACCCGCUGGGGCGUGUGAGCUGAUGCCCAGUGGAGUUGCCUCAUGUCAGGGAUGUGGCCAGGGCUUUAGACUCCUGCCUCGCUGCCCACCAGAUGUGUCUGAUUUGCCCAGGAAGGGCCUGACUCUGGCCAGACAGCCCUCUGCAACUCAGGCUGCCAGAAGUUCUGACACCUGGCCACACUGCCUGCAGCUGGGGAGCACGUCCUUCUGGCAAGGCGGAUUCCAGGGCGCGUGUAAAUCUCCACCACCAGCGCCGUGACUAUGCUGAGUCCCAGGCGGGUGCUCCCUGCCACCCGCCCCCACCCCUGCUGCACAUUCCUUCCCAGUAAAAACGCACACCCUCAGGACAGAGCAGUAUCUUCUAAAGGGCUUGCCCUUCACUUGGUUCUACCCAGAGAUAGAACCAUUCUAAGCAGUAACUCACAUGUAUGGAUUUCUUCUGGCAGAUCUGCAUGAGCUCUCAGUGAUGGUGGGGAAGGCGGGGACGGCAAAACUGCCAUCGCAUUUCCGAGGUGUGGCCCGCCUCCCUCAAGCUCCCGCACGGUUUCCCCAGGGGGUCCUCAUGCCCCUGCCCCUGGCCUGGUUUUGGUUCACCUGUUUCACCUGUUUCCCCUGACGCCUGCUCCACGCUUGGGCUUUCUGCUUUUUAUCUUUUCUUUAUUCUUAAUGGUUGACUUAUUUUCUUUACUCUCUUGUGUUUUUCAAGUUUUAAUUAAUGAGACUAUAUUACUUUAGUAGUGGAACACAGGUUGUCUAACAUUUUAUUGUGCACAUUUUUAAACAUACAGCAAUGUUUAAAGAGGUUUACGGUGAAAACCUGUCUGCUGUUAACACUUACGUAUGCCUGUGUCCUCACCACCUGUCACCUCUCUCUCUAUCUGUCCAUCAAUACACCCAUCCUCAAUUUAUCUGUUUUUUUUUUUUUUGCUACAUUUCAAAAUAAAUUUCAGAUGGCAAUGCAUUUCCCACUCCAUAUGUCAGCAUGCAUGUCAUUAUAACUAGAGUCCAAUACUAGCUUACUGUUUUAUUCCUUUGAAGCAAAAUUUGUAGUGUGAAACGCACAAGUACUAACAGCACCUUUGCUGAGUGUGGACAAAUAUGGACAUUGUGUGUAACUCAAAUCCCUGCCACAGUAGAGGACAUCACCAGCCUCCAGAAAGCUCACCAUGCCUCUUCCCAGGCAGUGCUUGACCCCACCUCUCCAAACAUAUCCACUAUUUUUAUUUCUUCCACCAUAAUGUAACUUACCUGUUUAGAAUUUUAUAUCCAAAAAAAAAACUUCACAAAAAAUGUAUACAAGAAUGUUCAUAGCUGCUUAAUCCGUAAGAGUUAAGAUUAGAAAGCCCAGGUGUCCAUCGAUAGGAUAGUAAACAAACGGUGGCACAUUCAUGCAAAGGUAGGUCACUCAGCCAUAAAAAGGAGGGGACGACUGAUAUACACAGCAAUAUGGGUGAUUCUCAAAAGCCUUGUGCUGGGUGGAAGAUACCUUCCCAAAAGAAUGCAUUCUGUACCAUGAUGUUUAAUCGCAUCCUUUCCUCCUUCCCAGCAGGCCACAUCUUAGGGCUUCCCUUAUAUCCACACACCGUAUUCCCUCCCGCUGGUGCACUUGAAGGUAAAGAAGCGAUGGCUGCCUUGCAGGGGGCAAGUCCUAAUUCCGUUUAUGGCAAGAUCUUGAGAAAUGCCAGACUUUAUUUUUUUUCUUUUAUUUUAGGUUCAGAGGUACAUGUGCAGGUUUGUUGUAUAGGUAACUCAUGUCAUGGGAGUUUGUUAUACAGAUCAUUUUGUCACCCAGGUACUAAGCCUAGUACCUAAUAGUUAUUUUUCUGCUCCUCUUCCUCCUCCCACCUUCCACCCCAAUGUCUGUUGUUCCUCUCUUUGUGUUCAUGAGUUCUCAUCAUUCAGCUUCCCCUUGUAAGUAAGAACAUGUGGUAUUUGGUUUUCUGUUUCUGUGUUAGUUUGCUAAAGAUAAUGGCCUCCAGCUCCAUCCAUGUUCCUGCAAAAGACAGGAUCUCAUUCUUUUUAUCAUUCUUUUUUAUGGCUGCACCAUUCCAUGGUGUAUAUGUACCACACUUUCUUUAUCCAGUCUGUCAUUGAUGGGCAUUUAGGUUGAUUCCAUGUCUUUGCUAUUGUGAAUAGUGUUGCAGUGAACAUUCUCAUGCAUGUGUCUUUAUGGUAGAAUGAUCCGUAUUCCUCUGGGAAUGUAUCCCGUUAUGGGAUUGCCAGACUUUAAUAGCAAUCAUAGCUCUCAUGUGUGCCCUGUCUGCAGGCUACCUGGCGACAUCAGUGGAGGAGGGCCCUCUCCCAGGCUAAACAGGUGUUUCUCUCUUUUGAGAGGUAUACCUUUAGAACUCCAAGGUGAGCUGACCAUUGCCUGCAAAUGGCGUGUCCUUACAUUCGUAUUAUAUUUUGCAGAAAAAGCGUGAAGUCAUACUAAAUAAGUCAACAAACGCUUUUACAACUGGGAAGAUGUCUCACCCCCCAAACAUUCCGAAGGAACAGACCCCAGCAGGGACGUCGAAUACAACCUCAGUCUCAGUAAAACCCUCUGAAGAGAAGACUUCUGAAAGCAAAAAGACUUACAACAGUAUCAGCAAAAUUGACAAAAUGUCCCGAAUCGUAUUCCCAGUCUUGUUCGGCACUUUCAACUUAGUUUACUGGGCAACGUAUUUGAAUAGGGAGCCGGUGAUAAAAGGAGCCGCCUCUCCAAAAUAACCGGCCACACUCCCAAACUCCAAGACAGCCAUACUUCCAGCGAAAUGGUACCAAGGAGAGGUCUUGCUCACAGGGACUCUCCAUAUGUGAGCACUAUCUUUCAGGAAAUUUUUGCAUGUUUAAUAAUAUGUACAAAUAAUAUUGCCUUGAUGUUUCUAUAUGUAACUUCAGAUGUUUCCAAGAUGUCCCAUUGAUAAUUCGAGCAAACAACUUUCUGGAAAAACAGGAUACGAUGACUGACACUCAGAUGCCCAGUAUCAUACGUUGAUAGUUUACAAACAAGAUACGUAUAUUUUUAACUGCUUCAAGUGUUACCUAACAAUGUUUUUUAUACUUCAAAUGUCAUUUCAUACAAAUUUUCCCAGUGAAUAAAUAUUUUAGGAAACUCUCCAUGAUUAUUAGUUGACCAACUAUAUUGCGAGAAACAGAGAUCAUAAAGAGCACGUUUUCCAUUAUGAGGAAACUUGGACAUUUAUGUACAAAAUGAAUUGCCUUUGAUAAUUCUUACUGUUCUGAAAUUAGGAAAGUACUGCAUGAUCUUACACGAAGAAAUAGAAUAGGCAAACUUUUAUGCAGGCAGAUUAAUAACAGAAAUACAUCAUAUGUUAGAUACACAAAAUAUUUCCCUGAGGAAAAAAAAUCAACUGCUUAAAUUUUUUGGGAAGAAAAAGAAACAUUUCUUACCCCACACCACCCACUACCUGAACAAUAGCCAAGAAAGGAAAGGAGAUGUUAAAACAAACAGUGUUUUGAUGACAUUCUCAGCACUUGGCCCAUGUGAUCGCUGUCUCUGAAACACUGACCACCUCUCCCUACAGCCAGCGUGUAGUGCUUCAGUGGUGAGAAAUUGUAAUUGAGUUAUUUUCCAUUUUAUUUCCUUGUAUGUAUUUCAUGACUGGACUUACUGCUCUGUCAGCUUUUGUAUAUGAAUCUUAAAUGUUCAUUAAAAAAUAAAAAAUGAACUGAUCUUGUGGA